GCAGUCGGUGCCAUCUUCUACGCCCCUGGGAGCGUUGUGGCUGCUGUUUCCUUCGGCUUUCCUCCUCCUGCUCCACCAUGUGGAGCCGACGGCAGGGCCGCCUCAGGCCCACGGUCUGCGGGGUGGAGGAGCUACGGCGCCGCCGGCGGGAGCGGGAGGCAGCACUGCGGAAGGCGCGGAGGGAGCAGCAGCUGGUCAGCAAGAGGCUGCUGAGAAACGACGCCCCAGAGGAAGCUGGAGAGGGAUGUGUGGCUGCGAUCCUCGGGGAAACCGAGGUGCAGCAGUUCCUGCGGCAAGCCCAGCGGGGGACAGAGGAAAAGGAGAGAGAGGGGGCUCUGGUCAGCCUUCGUCGAGGCUUGCAGCACCCUGAAACACAGCAAACCUUCAUCCGGCUGGAGGGCAGCAUGCGGACCCUGGUCGGGCUCCUGACCAGCAACCAGGCCCUGCUGCAGCUUGAGGCGGCUCGGUGCCUGCAUGAGCUCUCUCACUCCGAGCAGUCCACUGUUGCUGAGGCCUGCCUGCCAGCCACUUCUUACCUCCUCACCUACCUCUCCAGUCACAGCUCAGACUUCAUAGAGCUGUGUCUGUAUACACUGGGUAACCUGAUCGUGGAGAGUGAGGCUGUGAGAAGGCAGCUCCUGCCACAGGGCAUUGUUCCAGCCUUGGCUGCCUGCAUCCAGUCCCCCCAUGUGGCUGUGCUGGAAGCUCUCGGAUAUGCCUUGUCCCAGCUUCUACAGGCUGAGGAAGCUCCAGAGAAGAUCAUUCCCUCCAUCUUGGCCUCCACUCUCCCUCAGCACAUGCUACAAAUGUUGCAACCUGGCCCAAAGCUCAACCCUGGGGUCGCUGUGGAGUUUGCCUGGUGCCUUCAUUACAUCAUCUGCAGCCAGGUCAGCAAUCCUCUGCUCAUUGGCCAUGGGGCUCUGUCUACUCUGGGGUUGCUGCUGUUGGACUUGGCUGGGGCUGUCCAGAAAACCGAGGAUGCAGGACUGGAGCUGCUGGCAUGCCCCGUGCUUCGAUGUCUAAGCAACCUGCUAACUGAGGCAGCAGUGGAGACUGUGGGAGGGCAAAUGCAGCUCAGAGAUGAGCGUGUUGUGGCAGCCUUAUUUAUCCUUCUGCAGUUCUUUUUCCAGAAACAGCCCAGUCUGCUCCCUGAGGGCCUUUGGCUCCUCAACAACCUCACUGCAAACAGUCCUAGUUUCUGUACCUCCUUGCUCUCCCUGGAUCUGAUUGAGCCUCUCUUACAGCUGUUGCCAGUAUCUAACGUGGUGAGCGUAAUGUGAGAAAAGAAGAACACGCUUCCUCCUAACUAAUGAAGAUUAAAUGAGUUAGGCAGGGAAGCACUCAGCACAGGGCCCAGCUCUAUGUGCAAAAUUACUGAGAUUCUCACACACUACCUGGACUGACACUGGCUACACGUUAUUUGGAGAAACUAUAUUGACUAACUUCUCUCCUGUCUGAAGCCCAUUCUUAACUACAAAAACGUCAGCUCCUGGUCCCUACGCAGGAUUCGGUCAGCCUGCAUACUUAUGUUGCCCGGAAUACAACGCAUCAUAUAACCCUGCGAAUAUAAAUUUCUUCAUGGAAACAAGAUCAACAGCAAGGCUAAAGUCCGAGUUCUAGUUUCUCCACGGGUUUCUGCACGACCUUGGGCGGUCCCUUCUCUUCUCAAACCCUUGUUCCCCUACCGGAGCCCCAGACCCCUGGCGUCCCGCACUCACCGUAGCGGGCCCAGAGCUUGGGCUGCACAUCGGAGCAUUCGCGGAUUAGGAUGGGUAGGUCGGGAUUCGCCUUCUUCAGCUCCACGUAGCGUUUCUCAAUGAAGUCCCUGCGGGGCCGGAGAGAGCGCCGCGCGUGCUGUGGGCGGGGGCUUCCCUCAACUUCAGGGAGGUCGAGGUCGUGACCCUGGCGUCCCGAAGCCCGCCCGCCUCACCACGCCGCGCCUCACCUGACGCCCUGGCUGCCGGGCGAGCGCUGACAUAAGUGGAUGCGAAUCUCACGCAGGCCCAGCUUUGCCCCGACUCCUCGACUUGCUGCGGCCGCCGCCAUCCUUGUUAAUAUCGAAGUCGCCAAUUCCAGGUCUUCAGGCCAAGUGCUCCGGUCUGACCAACCGCGGACCCUAAAGCCUAGCCCAUAGGCUGCAUGAGGCAGGGGCGGGGUAAAGCUUGGCCAAUGAUAUAAAAGUAUUGUAGGACCGC